GAAACUGGUAACUUCGGGAGUUGAGCCACGAGCUGUUGUGCAUCCAGAGGUGGAAUUGGGGCCCGGCAUUCCCUCCUCGUCCCGGGCUGGCCCUUGCCCCCACCCUGCAACUCCUGGUUGAGAUGGGCUCAGCCAAGAGCGUCCCAGUCACACCAGCGCGGCCUCCGCCGCACAACAAGCAUCUGGCUCGAGUGGCGGACCCCCGUUCACCUAGUGCUGGCAUCCUGCGCACUCCCAUCCAGGUGGAGAGCUCUCCACAGCCAGGCCUACCAGCAGGGGAGCAACUGGAGGGUCUUAAACAUGCCCAGGACUCAGAUCCCCGCUCUCCUACUCUUGGUAUUGCACGGACACCUAUGAAGACCAGCAGUGGAGACCCCCCAAGCCCACUGGUGAAACAGCUGAGUGAAGUAUUUGAAACUGAAGACUCUAAAUCAAAUCUUCCCCCAGAGCCUGUUCUGCCCCCAGAGGCACCUUUAUCUUCUGAAUUGGACUUGCCUCUGGGUACCCAGUUAUCUGUUGAGGAACAGAUGCCACCUUGGAACCAGACUGAGUUCCCCUCCAAACAGGUGUUUUCCAAGGAGGAAGCAAGACAGCCCACAGAAACCCCUGUGGCCAGCCAGAGCUCCGACAAGCCCUCAAGGGACCCUGAGACUCCCAGAUCUUCAGCCUCCUCAGUUCCAGAUUUUGAGGAAGCUGUCCCAGGAACCUGUGGCCACAGCCAUCCCGUCAGCUGUGACUCCCAGGCAGCUCACCCUGUUAUCGUGGCCAGAGAGGAUGCCUGAGGAAGAGGGAAAGGAGUCAGCCUGUCUCUCCAAGCUGAUUUGGAAAGCAGUGUGUGCAUGCGUGUAAGUGUAUGUGUGGGUGUGUGGGUGUGUGUGUGUAUGUGGGUGUGUGGGGGGAUAUGUGUGCAUGUGUAUGCAUGUGUGGGUGUGUGUACGUGUGUGUGUGCAUGUGUGCUUGAGCACAUGCAUGCAGGGAUCCUAGACUCGGUAGACUGGGCUCAACCCCUGAAGAAGGCUAAGAGACUGAAAGAGGAUUAGCUGUAGGGCAGGGGGUUCUCUGUCAAGAGCUUUGGUUGGGGGAGGGCUGGGAUCAGACAGAGAAAGGCUGGAAGCAUCUGUGUACUAUGAAAAAACCCGAGGGCACCUUGACAGGUGCUGGAAAAGAGAAGGCAACCGUUCAUCCUAUUUCUUUGCUUCCAGAUGAAGAAACUGAGGCCCAUGGAGGAGUGACUUGUGCAAGGACACUCAGAAAGUGAGCAACAGAAUUAGGAUUUGGAUUCUGCCCCUGGCCAGUGUUAUUUUCAUCAGCACCUGGCCUCUUGAUAGAGAAGAAGCCAUCCUAUCUGACCAACUUCAGGCUAGUCUUAGAUGAGCCCUAGGCUGCAGUCAGGGCCCUCGGGCCACUCCAGAUCUCCUUGAUUCUGCCUUGAUUCCAUGUUUCCCUGAGGCUGUCUUGCCUCUCAGUGGGUGCCCCUGAAAUGCCAGGAACCCAGAACUGACUGGACAGUCAUGGUCCACAGAUCUCCUAGGGCAGGGAGCAGUCAUGGCAUUGGGCAGUGGAGAGAGGCUGCUUAGAGCAACACUGAGGGAAAACAGUCCUAGUUGGGAACCAAGGGGUACUGGAUUCCAGGGGUGGAGUCACCCAGUGACAAGGGACAGCAGUAAGAGAGUCCGAAAUGGGAGCUGAUGGGGGGUACAGAAUGGGGAGGGAGGGCUGGGGAGGGUCCUUCCAGCUGAGGAAGCAGCAGCCAGGGCUGGCCCUUACCCACACGCUCAGACUUCAUGGAGUCCCAGACAUUGCAGUUGAAGUCGUCGUAGCCAGCGAAUAGUAGGCGGCCACUGAGGGAGAAGGCCACGGACGUGAUGCCGCAGAUGAUGCUCUCGUGGGAGAAGCAGAUCAGCUCCUGGUCUGCCCGCAGGUCAAACAAGCGGCAGGAAGCGUCAUCCGAGCCCGUGCAGAUGGCCUCUCCAUUGGGGAAGAACUGAGGGCACGGGUGGCAAGUGGGUCAGGGAUCAGACCUGGGCAGCCCACAGCCUCUCCCGCCCUCUGCCUCCCACCUGACAGCUCCAGGGCAAGCCGCUGCUCUCAGCCUCCCUGCCUGUCCCUCCCUUGGUUUGGGGUGAGAAGCAGCCCUGCCAACACAUACCACGUGCCAGUGACUUCCCUAUGCCCCUCGCCCGCUCUGCACUAUACAGCGCUGCAGGCAGGCAUCAUUUCCACGUCGCAGGCAAGAGCACCAAGGCUUGCCUGCAGUGACCCGGCUAGAAGGGCGGACGGAGGUUGUCCCAGACUCCCAGACUACACAAGUGGGCUGGAUCAGGGUGUGUAAGAACAGGGUCCAGUACAAAUGCAAGGCCUGGAUCUCACGGCGAGCAAAUGUCAGAUAAGCUCAAACGGAGGGAGAGUCUACAGAAAACUGGUUUGUACUCUUCAAAAACGUCAAUGACAUAAAAGACAAAGGUGGGAAAACAGUUCCAGUUUAAAGGUGGUGACGAAAAAGAUAUGGCGAGGAAAGGUAAUGCACGUUUCUGGAUUGGAUCCUGGACAGAAAAAAACAUGAGCUAUUAUGGACAUUUUUGAGGCUAUUGGUGAAAUUUGAAUAUAGACUGUAGACUGUAGUAUUGUGUCAAUGUUGAGUUUCCUGAUCUUAAGAAUCAUACAGUGAUUAUGCUACAGAAGGGCUUUGUUUCGGGAAGUACUUAAGGGGUAAAGAAACAUGAUGUCUGCAACCUACUUUCAAAAGACACAGAAAGAAAAUGUAUAUCUACA